AGAGGCAUUCUGAACUUCAGCACAAGGCAAACGCAGAACCAGGGCUUGGAAUUUCGCCGCUAUGCAGCUGCACCCCUGCCACCCAGGAGAUCUGAGGCUCCUCAGAGCUGGGAGGACCGGGUCAGUGCCAUGGCGGGGAAUGGGACGUGAGCCUUGCCUGGGUGAGGCUCUGGGUUUUCUGUUCUGCCUCUGAGGUGUGCUGUCUGAGUGACAGGGGUGGUGAGGGGCGGGGGCAGUGUGUCUCCGGGAUUCCAGCUCCUCCUCAGCCCAAGCCUUGGCAGGUGAGUUCUGUUCAUCCUGAGUGCCUGGACCCUCCCUGACCCACCUGCCCACAGGUGCAGUGGCCGGGGUGUCACCGCUUUCUGCUUCCCCUGACCAUGGCUUGCCCCUGGCACUUAGGAGGGUGCCCCCAGGAUGGCAGCAAGGGCUGUACCCUGGGACGUCAGAGGUCUACUCUUUUUACCCACCUGAGAGUUUCAGCAUCUCUCUUGGGGGCUUUCUGGAUCCAGCCCACCAACUCCGUUUGGACAUCCUGACAGGUGGGGAGACCUGUGUUUAGGAGAAGCCUGUGCCUGGGUAUCAGGCCAGCUGGGAGUAUUUUCUCUCCCAGAGUAGAUCCACCACCAGGGGGCAGCAUCUCUUCCAGGAGGGGAAGACCCAUUUUACCCAGCGUCAGAGACACUGGCCAGCGCUGUUGAGGACGGAUCUGCAGCCCCAGAGAGGCCUGGAGGCCUCGUGGCUUGCCCACGUUUGAAGGCCAAGUGCAGAGCCCUGUGACAGUCCUGGUCAACUCAGAAGAUUGAAGAAGGAGAGUGAGGGUCCCAAACACUCUGCCUCCCCAACCCAGGCCUGCGAGUGGCAGUGUGGGCAGGCGGUGGGGCCAGAGCAGCCCGCAGCCCGGAACCAGGGCAGGACAGCGCACCUGGCCUGCCUUUGAAUUGGGGUCACCAGCGGGCUUCGGCCAGGGCUGUCUCAGGAUGCUGGUGGCACGGGGCAGAGAGGGCAUGGUGACUGUUCAUGGACACAGCAGCCCCUCGAGGAGGAGGCUGGAGCCAUCCUCAUAUGGAGGAGAAGCAGGCAUGGUGGUGGCCCUAGCCCUAGGGAAGGGUGGGCCGCACCCUUCCUUCAGGAGAGCGAGUGGCCAGCUGCUGUGGCCCUCACAUGGAGGGUGAGGGCUGGCCCGAGCACCUGGCCAUCAAUGUCCUCAAGCAAAGGGGAGGGCAACUACCUAAUAAUAUUACCUUUUAGCUAUUUCUCUAGGCAGGUUCCCCUACCUGAAAAGAUUGCCCCCGGCUUCAGAGUGUUUCAAGAUGCCUGAAGUUCUAACACCAGAGAUGGUUUCCUGCUGCUUCCAGGAACAGGGUCUGUUCUUAGUCCAAUGUGGAGUUCCUCAUGGGGACCCCAUUCCCCAGGAAUCCAGGUUCCACAGUACUCUGACUUGGUCUGGCUGGUCUCGGCUGGCACUUUCCCUAGGACUGCUAAAACCACGGUGAGGGCGGAGAGCUGAGGGCCGAAGAAGGCGGGGCAUCUCUGCCGGCCUUGCCACAACCGUGAGAAGGCCAAGGGCCUGGGCAAGUACAUCUGCCAGCGGUGCCACCUGGUCAUCGACGAGCAGCCCCUCAUGUUCAGGAGCGACGCCUACCACCCUGACCACUUCAACUGCACCCACUGUGGGAAGGAGCUGACAGCCGAGGCCCGCGAGCUGAAGGGUGAGCUCUACUGCCUGCCCUGCCAUGACAAGAUGGGCGUCCCCAUCUGCGGGGCCUGCCGCCGGCCCAUCGAGGGCCGAGUGGUCAACGCGCUGGGCAAGCAGUGGCACGUGGAGCACUUUGUCUGUGCCAAGUGUGAGAAGCCAUUCCUGGGGCACCGGCACUAUGAGAAGAAGGGCCUGGCCUACUGCGAGACUCACUACAACCAGCUCUUCGGGGACGUCUGCUACAACUGCAGCCAUGUGAUUGAAGGCGAUGUGGUGUCGGCCCUCAACAAGGCCUGGUGUGUGAGCUGCUUCUCCUGCUCCACCUGCAACAGCAAGCUCACCCUGAAGAACAAGUUUGUGGAGUUCGACAUGAAGCCCGUGUGUAAGAGGUGCUACGAGAAGUUCCCGCUGGAGCUGAAGAAGCGGCUGAAGAAGCUGUCGGAGCUGACCUCCCGCAAGGCCCAGCCCAAGGCCACAGACCUCAACUCUGCCUGAAGGCCCUCUUGCGCAGCUGCCUCUCGGCCCCUCCGCCUUCUCCCCUCCUGCUGUCCAUGCUUGGCCCCCUCGUCCCCAUCCACCUGUGCCCUCCGCAUCUUACCCUCCCUUUCUCUUUCCUCAUUGCCUUCUCCCUUCCUGUUCCCUCAUCUCUGCCUUCCCCAUGUCUCUCCUCUCCUUGGCCGUGGCUUCUGUCUGUGAGGAGGCAGGAGCUGGGGAGUGGGAGCCUAUGACCCCACGUCUGACAGCCAUGUCCACCUGUGCCCACAGCUUCCGCCCACAGACCUCCAGGGACAGGAGCAAAUUGCACCACAGCUCCCCGCCUGGCCUGGCCCUCCCCAGGCGGCUCAGUGGCUCAUGCUGUCCUGUGAGAGCCCCUGCCCCAGAGCGGCCCCACUAAGCGCAUGUGGCUCCUGGGCUACCCACAGCCAGGGCAGCCUGCUGGAGCCACAGGGCCAGGGCCAUGCAGAUGGAGGCCUCUGGGAGCCACCUCCAAUCCCUCACCACUCACUCAACCAGUGGCACAGUGUCCUUGUGCCCACACUGAGCCAGCAAGUCCUGCUGUCCACACCCACAAGCUACCUGGAGGGACAGGACCCACCUCCAUCCUUCGGAAGGCCUUCCUGGAAUCCCACCUUGGCCUCCGCCCUCGGUUCCGCCCCGCCCCUCUCCCCCCGACCUUGGGGCUUGUGUCGAGCCCUUGGGUGGGGCCAGGAGGAGGUGAUGGCGUCAGAGGAGGUGUGGUCAGAGGUGACUUGUUCCCACCUCCAGGGAGGACGCUUCGUCUUCGGCCAGCGCAGACCUGGUGUUUGUUUGUUGGGCUCACGCUUGCACAAUGAAGGCUUGUUCACACAA